GCAGCCUGGCGGAGACGGGAGGAGGAGCGGAGGGAGAAGUAGGUUGCGAGCUCAGCACAGGCUCCGGCGCUGGCUCCCGCAGCUGAGUUUGGGAGAUGUCUAAGUGAUUUUUUUUUUUUCCCGGAAGGCAAAUGGCUGGCGUGGAAGCACAACCCGCUUUCACUCUUCGAAUUUGUGCUUAGCUCUUUUCUUGUACCUUGCGACUCGUGACCAACAUGCUGUGAUGUGUGCCGAGGGAGGAAUUGGUCAGCUACACAACCUGGAUCUUACCACAGUUUGGAUAUGACUGAGGCUCUCCAAUGGGCCAGAUAUCACUGGCGACGGCUGAUCAGAGGUGCAACCAGGGAUGAUGAUUCAGGGCCAUACAACUAUUCCUCGUUGCUCGCCUGUGGGCGCAAGUCCUCUCAGACCCCUAAACUGUCAGGAAGGCACCGGAUUGUUGUUCCCCACAUCCAGCCCUUCAAGGAUGAGUAUGAGAAGUUCUCCGGAGCCUAUGUGAACAAUCGAAUACGAACAACAAAGUACACACUUCUGAAUUUUGUGCCAAGAAAUUUAUUUGAACAAUUUCACAGAGCUGCCAAUUUAUAUUUCCUGUUCCUAGUUGUCCUGAACUGGGUACCUUUGGUAGAAGCCUUCCAAAAGGAAAUCACCAUGUUGCCUCUGGUGGUGGUCCUUACAAUUAUCGCAAUUAAAGAUGGCCUGGAAGAUUAUCGGAAAUACAAAAUUGACAAACAGAUCAAUAAUUUAAUAACUAAAGUUUAUAGUAGGAAAGAGAAAAAAUACAUUGACCGAUGCUGGAAAGACGUUACUGUUGGGGACUUUAUUCGCCUCUCCUGCAACGAGGUCAUCCCUGCAGACAUGGUACUACUCUUUUCCACUGAUCCAGAUGGAAUCUGUCACAUUGAGACUUCUGGUCUUGAUGGAGAGAGCAAUUUAAAACAGAGGCAGGUGGUUCGGGGAUAUGCAGAACAGGACUCUGAAGUUGAUCCUGAGAAGUUUUCCAGUAGGAUAGAAUGUGAAAGCCCAAACAAUGACCUCAGCAGAUUCCGAGGCUUCCUAGAACAUUCCAACAAAGAACGCGUGGGUCUCAGUAAAGAAAAUUUGUUGCUUAGAGGAUGCACCAUUAGAAACACAGAGGCUGUUGUGGGCAUUGUGGUUUAUGCAGGCCAUGAAACCAAAGCAAUGCUGAACAACAGUGGGCCACGGUAUAAGCGCAGCAAAUUAGAAAGAAGAGCAAACACAGAUGUCCUCUGGUGUGUCAUGCUUCUGGUCAUAAUGUGCUUAACUGGCGCAGUAGGUCAUGGAAUCUGGCUGAGCAGGUAUGAAAAGAUGCAUUUUUUCAAUGUUCCCGAGCCUGAUGGACAUAUCAUAUCACCACUGUUGGCAGGAUUUUAUAUGUUUUGGACCAUGAUCAUUUUGUUACAGGUCUUGAUUCCUAUUUCUCUCUAUGUUUCCAUCGAAAUUGUGAAGCUUGGACAAAUAUAUUUCAUUCAAAGUGAUGUGGAUUUCUACAAUGAAAAAAUGGAUUCUAUUGUUCAGUGCCGAGCCCUGAACAUCGCCGAGGAUCUGGGACAGAUUCAGUACCUCUUUUCCGAUAAGACAGGAACCCUCACUGAGAAUAAGAUGGUUUUUCGAAGAUGUAGUGUGGCAGGAUUUGAUUACUGCCAUGAAGAAAAUGCCAGGAGGUUGGAGUCCUAUCAGGAAGCUGUCUCUGAAGAUGAAGAUUUUAUAGACACAGUCAGUGGUUCCCUCAGCAAUAUGGCAAAACCGAGAGCCCCCAGCUGCAGGACAGUUCAUAAUGGGCCUUUGGGAAAUAAGCCCUCAAAUCAUCUUGCUGGGAGCUCUUUUACUCUAGGAAGUGGAGAAGGAGCCAGUGAAGUGCCUCAUUCCAGACAGGCUGCUUUCAGUAGCCCCAUUGAAACAGACGUGGUACCAGACACCAGGCUUUUAGACAAAUUUAGUCAGAUUACACCUCGGCUCUUUAUGCCACUAGAUGAGACCAUCCAAAAUCCACCAAUGGAAACUUUGUACAUUAUCGACUUUUUCAUUGCAUUGGCAAUUUGCAACACAGUAGUGGUUUCUGCUCCUAACCAACCCCGACAAAAGAUCAGACACCCUUCACUGGGGGGGUUGCCCAUUAAGUCUUUGGAAGAGAUUAAAAGUCUUUUCCAGAGAUGGUCUGUCCGAAGAUCAAGUUCUCCAUCGCUUAACAGUGGGAAAGAGCCAUCUUCUGGAGUUCCAAACGCCUUUGUGAGCAGACUCCCUCUCUUUAGUCGAAUGAAACCAGCUUCACCUGUGGAGGAAGAGGUCUCCCAGGUGUGUGAGAGCCCCCAGUGCUCCAGUAGCUCAGCUUGCUGCACAGAAACAGAGAAACAACACGGUGAUGCAGGCCUCCUGAAUGGCAAGGCAGAGUCCCUCCCUGGACAGCCAUUGGCCUGCAACCUGUGUUAUGAGGCCGAGAGCCCAGACGAAGCGGCCUUAGUGUAUGCCGCCAGGGCUUACCAAUGCACUUUACGGUCUCGGACACCAGAGCAGGUCAUGGUGGACUUUGCUGCUUUGGGACCAUUAACAUUUCAACUCCUACACAUCCUGCCCUUUGACUCAGUAAGAAAAAGAAUGUCUGUUGUGGUCCGACACCCUCUUUCCAAUCAAGUUGUGGUGUAUACGAAAGGCGCUGAUUCUGUGAUCAUGGAGUUACUGUCGGUGGCUUCCCCAGAUGGAGCAAGUCUGGAGAAACAACAGAUGAUAGUAAGGGAGAAAACCCAGAAGCACUUGGAUGACUAUGCCAAACAAGGCCUUCGUACUUUAUGUAUAGCAAAGAAGGUCAUGAGUGACACUGAAUAUGCAGAGUGGCUGAGGAAUCAUUUUUUAGCUGAAACCAGCAUUGACAACAGGGAAGAAUUACUACUUGAAUCUGCCAUGAGGUUGGAGAACAAACUUACAUUACUUGGUGCUACUGGCAUUGAAGACCGUCUGCAGGAGGGAGUCCCUGAAUCUAUAGAAGCUCUUCACAAAGCGGGCAUCAAGAUCUGGAUGCUGACAGGGGACAAGCAGGAGACAGCUGUCAACAUAGCUUAUGCAUGCAAACUACUGGAGCCAGAUGACAAGCUUUUUAUCCUCAAUACCCAAAGUAAAGAUGCCUGUGGGAUGCUGAUGAGCACAAUUUUGAAAGAACUUCAGAAGAAAACUCAAGCCCUGCCAGAGCAAGUGUCAUUAAGUGAAGAUUUACUUCAGCCUCCUGUCCCCCGGGACUCAGGGUUACGAGCUGGACUCAUUAUCACUGGGAAGACCCUGGAGUUUGCCCUGCAAGAAAGUCUGCAAAAGCAGUUCCUGGAACUGACAUCUUGGUGUCAAGCUGUGGUCUGCUGCCGAGCCACACCGCUGCAGAAAAGUGAAGUGGUGAAAUUGGUCCGCAGCCAUCUCCAGGUGAUGACCCUUGCUAUUGGUGAUGGUGCCAAUGAUGUUAGCAUGAUACAAGUGGCAGACAUUGGGAUAGGGGUCUCAGGUCAAGAAGGCAUGCAGGCUGUGAUGGCCAGUGACUUUGCCGUUUCUCAGUUCAAACAUCUCAGCAAGCUCCUUCUUGUCCAUGGACACUGGUGUUAUACACGGCUUUCCAACAUGAUUCUCUAUUUUUUCUAUAAGAAUGUGGCCUAUGUGAACCUCCUUUUCUGGUACCAGUUCUUUUGUGGAUUUUCAGGAACAUCCAUGACUGAUUACUGGGUUUUGAUCUUCUUCAACCUCCUCUUCACAUCUGCCCCUCCUGUCAUUUAUGGUGUUUUGGAGAAAGAUGUGUCUGCAGAGACCCUCAUGCAACUGCCUGAACUUUACAGAAGUGGUCAGAAAUCAGAGGCAUACUUACCCCAUACCUUCUGGAUCACCUUAUUGGAUGCUUUUUAUCAAAGCCUGGUCUGCUUCUUUGUGCCUUAUUUUACCUACCAGGGCUCAGAUACUGACAUCUUUGCAUUUGGAAACCCCCUGAACACAGCCGCUCUGUUCAUCGUUCUCCUCCAUCUGGUCAUUGAAAGCAAGAGUUUGACUUGGAUUCACUUGCUGGUCAUCAUUGGUAGCAUCUUGUCUUAUUUUUUAUUUGCCAUAGUUUUUGGAGCCAUGUGUGUAACUUGCAACCCACCAUCCAACCCUUACUGGAUUAUGCAGGAGCACAUGCUGGAUCCAGUAUUCUACUUAGUUUGUAUCCUCACGACGUCCAUUGCUCUUCUGCCCAGGUUUGUAUACAGAGUUCUUCAGGGAUCCCUGUUUCCAUCUCCAAUUCUGAGAGCUAAGCACUUUGACAGACUAACUCCAGAGGAGAGGACUAAAGCUCUCAAGAAGUGGAGAGGGGCUGGAAAGAUGAAUCAAGUGACAUCAAAGUAUGCUAACCAAUCAGCUGGCAAGUCAGGAAGAAGACCCAUGCCUGGCCCUUCUGCUGUAUUUGCAAUGAAGUCAGCAAGUUCCUGUGCUAUUGAGCAAGGAAACUUAUCUCUGUGUGAAACUGCUUUAGAUCAAGGCUACUCUGAAACUAAGGCCUUUGAGAUGGCUGGACCCUCCAAAGGUAAAGAAAGCUAGAUACCCUCCUUGGAGUUGCAAGUAUUCUUUCAAGGUUGGAAGAGGGAUUUUGAAGAGGUAUCUCUCCAAGCAAGAAUGACUUGUUUUUCCAUAAGGGACAUGAGCAUUUUACUAGGCUUGGAAGAGCUGACAUGAUGAGCAUUAUUGUAUGUUUGUAUAUACAUUUGUGAUAGAGGGCUAGAGUUUGACCUAGAGAGAGUUUAAGGAAGUGAAAUAUUUAAUUCAGAACCAAAUGCUUUUGUAAAACUUUUUGGAUUUUGUAAAAGCAUUUUCAUUCUCUUAGAAAUUCAAGUAUUUUCAAGGGGAGUCAUUUGAGAUAUAUUUAUUUUACUAGGAGAUCUUAUAUUCUAGGGAAAUGCUUUAAAUGGUCAGGCUCCAGUCGGAAUUUUUUUAAGAAAAAAGUAGUUUUUAAUACAUUGGUUAGGACUCAGAGGAAAUACGGAAAAAACAUUGUAGAUGGUUAAUUUACAGAUAAAAUCCCAAGAGCCUUUUAAACAACAAGGUACCUAAAAUAGGGUAUAAUUAUACUGCUUAAAAUACAGUUAGUGCCUAUUAAUAGCUUUUUAUUUCCUAUGGGAAGAUGCUUUUGGUCUUCUGGCUGAAGAUGUAGGCAUACCUCUCACUCAUUUCAAUGUUUUCCUGAGGUGGAGCCUUCAUUGGAAAGGGGAAAGAGGGAUUCUAGGGUUUCAUCAGGGACCAGGAAUGCAUUCCUCUGUCAGGUUCCAAUCAAGAGAAGACCUUUUAUGAGAUCUGCCUCUGUAUAGAUGUUGUCAGUUAGGAAACUGAAGCCAUAGGUCAGGCAGACAUCAGCUCAGCCUGUGGCCCAUUGGGUGAUUUCCUGUAUUUUAAAACUGACAGUAGCCUGAUCAAAGUGAUACAAUCAAUUUCAAAACAAUCUUCCAGAGACCACUUGAAGGUUCAUAGUUUUUACAAUACCCUGAGACUUUUCAGGUGUUGGAGCCUCUAAAAUAUGAGAUAUAAACAGAAACUAAUACAAGUUGUUCUCUGGAGGUUUCUAUGAGGUUCUUAGAAAAAUUUGGUUUUAAAAUCAUUUGAGGACAGGAAUGUCUAUAGCAAGUUUACUCCUAUUGCGAAUCAUGUAUGCUGGCUUUAGUUGUAACAAACGAUUUUAUUCUAAGUAAGGCCAGGUGCUACUAUAAAAUCAUAUAUUCCUGUUGAAGUUCUUUUGAAGUCCUAUCUCUAUUUAUUAUAUUUGAAAGUUGUCAGCCACCAGUCAUCCAGAAUUUCCUUCCUGAAUCUCCAUGCUCAUAUGCAAUGUCUACAUCAAGGUCUUCUUAAUGACUAUUAUUCUCAGGGUUUAGUUUUCUACCUUCUGCCUACUAUUUUGGUCUGACAUUUUUGUAGCCUUCUGUUAUUAUUGGAAAUAGUCUCUUACAUAAGCUGAUUUCGAGAACUUUCAAAAUCUCACAUAGCUAAUGGAAGUUGCUUUCUGCUUUCUUAUGACUGUUUUUAUAAAUAAACUGUUUCAUAAAUAAUGUAUACUGGAAAAUUGUCAUCACUCUUGUAAACAUUUGCCAAAUCCAACUGUAAUUAGUACCAGAACUUAGAAGGAAAGUCACAAAGCAUGCCUUUUACCAGAAUAUUGCUUUGCCUUUUCUUAUAUGGAAAAUCACUGAUGUCAUAUCAUUUAUUAUCCUCACAGCAGCUGGCAUUCAUUCCCUGAAAUCGUCGUCUCCUGAUAAACAAUAAUUUAGAGAUAUGUUCACUUGUAAAUAAAAAGGUUAGAAUCUAAGGACAAAGAAUGAUCCAAAAAUACUAAGGAAAAAGAACAAUUUUCAAUUUUCAGAAAUGAAUUAUCUGUACAUAUGAAUAGAGGAAAAUACUGAGUGCUAAUGUUACAGGGCCACAAUCUCAUAUCCACAAUUCCAAAAUCUCCAAACCUCUGAAAACUGAAAUAUUUUUCAUAAAUUAGGCGUAAAUUCUAUGCCCUGAACAAAUGUAAAGCUAUUUAUGUACUUUGCUUAAUGUAAUCAUUCAUAUACUUUGCUACAAAAAUAUUAAUAUAUUUCAUUACUGAAUGCUAAACUGUAUUUCUUUUUAAAAUUUGGAAAAUUUUUAAUUCUGAAACACAAUCUAGACCUUAG